AGUACUUUUCCAGCAUUUUCUCAUUUAUUACAACAGUUCCCUCGAGAACAGUAGAGAAACACCCAGGUUUUGGCAUUCAGCAAACCUGAAUGUGAUUCCUGGCUCCAUCUCUGACAAGCUUUGUGACAACAGGGUCAAAGUCAGAGUGGUGGUCAUGGUCCUGGAGGUGGCAAGAAGGAUGACAAGGACAAGAAAAAGAAAUAUGAACCUCCUGUACCAACUAGAGUGGGGAAAAAGAAGAAGAAAACAAAGGGACCAGAUGCUGCCAGCAAACUGCCACUGGUGACACCUCACACUCAGUGCCGGUUAAAAUUACUGAAGUUAGAGAGAAUUAAAGACUAUCUUCUCAUGGAGGAAGAAUUCAUUAGAAAUCAGGAACAAAUGAAACCAUUAGAAGAAAAGCAAGAGGAGGAAAGAUCAAAAGUGGAUGAUCUGAGGGGGACCCCGAUGUCAGUAGGAACCUUGGAAGAGAUCAUUGAUGACAAUCAUGCCAUCGUGUCUACAUCUGUGGGCUCAGAACACUACGUCAGCAUUCUUUCAUUUGUAGACAAGGAUCUGCUGGAACCUGGCUGCUCGGUCCUGCUCAACCACAAGGUGCAUGCCGUGAUAGGGGUGCUGAUGGAUGACACGGAUCCCCUGGUCACAGUGAUGAAGGUAGAAAAGGCCCCCCAGGAGACCUAUGCAGAUAUUGGGGGGUUGGACAACCAAAUUCAGGAAAUUAAGGAAUCUGUGGAGCUUCCUCUCACCCAUCCUGAAUAUUAUGAAGAGAUGGGUAUAAAGCCUCCUAAGGGGGUCAUUCUCUAUGGUCCACCUGGCACAGGUAAAACCUUGUUAGCCAAAGCAGUAGCAAACCAAACCUCAGCCACUUUCUUGAGAGUGGUUGGCUCUGAACUUAUUCAGAAGUACCUAGGUGAUGGGCCCAAACUCGUACGGGAAUUGUUCCGAGUUGCUGAAGAACAUGCACCGUCCAUCGUGUUUAUUGAUGAAAUUGACGCCAUUGGGACAAAAAGAUAUGACUCCAAUUCUGGUGGUGAGAGAGAAAUUCAGCGAACAAUGUUGGAACUGCUGAACCAGUUGGAUGGAUUUGAUUCUAGGGGAGAUGUGAAAGUUAUCAUGGCCACAAACCGAAUAGAAACUUUGGAUCCAGCACUUAUCAGACCAGGCCGCAUUGACAGGAAGAUUGAGUUCCCCCUGCCUGAUGAAAAGACGAAGAAGCGCAUCUUUCAGAUUCACACAAGCAGGAUGACGCUGGCUGAUGAUGUAACCCUGGACGACCUGAUCAUGGCUAAAGAUGACCUCUCUGGUGCUGACAUCAAGGCAAUCUGUACAGAAGCUGGUCUGAUGGCCUUAAGAGAACGUAGAAUGAAAGUAACAAAUGAAGACUUCAAAAAAUCUAAAGAAAAUGUUCUUUAUAAGAAACAGGAAGGCACCCCUGAGGGGCUGUAUCUCUAAUGAACCAUGGCUGUCAUCAGGAAAAUGGUUGGGAGAUUUCUCAAUCCCUGAAAGGGAUGAGGUUGGGGGAGUUGCCCAGAGGAAUCCCUGUUCCCACUGAUUUUUAUUAGCAAAACAUCCUGUGUCUUUUGGAGUACGAUGUGUAAGUGCCCAUUGGGUGGCCUGUUGGUCACUGUGCAGCAGUCUGCUUCCCAAUAAAGCGUGCUCUUUCACAAACACUUCCUGUUUCUGCAGUCUCCACACACACCUACCGCUCAACAGCAGCCUGUGGGUGGACCCAGCUACAGGGAAGCCUUUGGACAGGAACUCAGGCUGCGGUCCCAAGGAGUGUGGACCUCACUAUGCGUUCGCCACAUCACACCCCCAGAGCUGGCGUUCAACGGUAAUUACAGUGGGAAAUGGUCACUACCACAGAGCCAGGGAUAUUCGUUGUUUAAAUAAUAAAGGCUGCGUUAAUGUGGCUAUUGCUUCCAAAGGAAGUACAGCUUUCCUUUUUGGAAGUUUUGUGGACCAUGCAUGUUCUUAGCACUCUGAGGGCAGAAAAUAACUACUGGUGUUCCCAAGAGACUGAGGAUUCCUAGAGAUAUCUUGAAAGCCCUUCUGAGCCCUUGGGCUCAGAAAUCUCAUCCCUUUCAAGGUGUUCAGAAACAUGUCAGAACUUCCCCUUCCCUUUCUCCGUCUAUUUCCGUCAUUUCUCUUUCUGAACAAAUCAGGCCUAAAGCUAUUAAGUGGGACAGAUCAAGGUAAGCGUUCCCUUGACAGGUGGCCUGGUGUGGGUUGUAGGGCCCACACUGAAUGAGGAGUGUGUAUUAGUUUUCUGUUAAUACUAUAACAAGUUACCACAGGCUUUGUUUAAAAACAGCACAAUUUGGCCAGGCACGGUGGCUCACGCCUGUAAUCCCAGCACUUUGGGAAGCUGAGGCAGGCGGAUCACAAGGUCAGAAGUUUGAGGCCAGCCUGGCCAACAUGGUGAAACCCCAUCUUUACUAAAAAUACAAAAAUUAGCUGUGCGUGGUGGCAGGUGCCUGUAGUCCCAGCUACUCAGGAGGCUGAGGCAGGACAAUCGCUUGAACCCAGGAGGCGGAGGUUGCAGUGAGCCAAGAUCCCGUCACUGCACUCCAGCCUGGGCGACAGAGCAAGACUCCGUCUCAAAAAUAAAUAAAUAAAUAAAUAAAAACCACAAUUUUAUCUCAGUUCUGUAGGUCAGAAGUCCAACACGAGUGUCUCCAGGCUAAAGUCUUGCUGUUGGCAGGACCGUUCCCUCUGGCGUCUCUAAGGGAGAAUCCGUUUCCUUGCUGAGGAUUAUUGUUGGCAGAAUUUAAUUUCUUGGAGUUGUGGGCCAGCUGAGGUCAGCAUUUCCUUGCUGGCUGCCAGCUGAGGCCUUUGCCAGUCUGUGAAGGCCACCCUCCCUCCUGACUCGUGGCACUUCAUUUUCCACCAGCAGCAGCAGGCCCAGUCCCUCUCUCCCACCGACCCUUCUUUCUGCCUGCCUUUUCUAUUCUUAUGGAUCCUUGUGAUUGCAUUGGACCCAUGCAGAUGAUCCAGGAUAAUUUCCCUGUUUUAAAGUUUACAAUCUUCUUAAUUUUUAUCUGCAAAGUUCCUUUUGCCAUGUAACAUUCACACGUUCCAGGGCUUAGGGUGUGGCCAUCUUUAGGGGCGCCACUCUGCCUACCACAGAGGACAUCCACACGUGGGGGUGGCCCAGUGCAGGGUAAGGACGGGGUGCUUGUGGGGAGGGCGGGUGUCAGCCCAAGUAGGGUGUGGAGCUGUCCAUGUGGAGGAACACCACAGCACGGGGACUCAGCAUGGGCAGGGUGAGGCUGGCAUCCGUGUGGGGUGUAUGUGCAGGGCUGGGGUGGUCCGAUAGGGGGAGUCAGUGUGGGCAGCCUGAUGUGCAGUAUGAGAGCCCAAGUGGGUGAGGAAGGCAUCUGCAGGGACGGGGUGGUGGCAGGGGAGGGAGGCUGCUUAUGUAUGGAGGCAGUCAGGCAGGUAAACAGGACAGUGGGAGCCAGGUUUCUCUGAGGAGUUAGACACAGAAAGAAGAAAACAAGAACGACCUCUGUCCACUGGGAGCACCUGGGAACAGUGACACCCCAACUGCAGUGAGCACCCCUAGACCCAGACCUUUGCUGCUAAAAGUAUUAUUCUCCACUAAAAGGAGUGAGGGCUGAUUCCGGGGCUAGGCAGGGAAAGGACAGGAUGAACCCAAAGUCUGUUUUGCCAGAAAGCAAGGGAGUGCUCAAGGAAUGAUAAGGACAUGUCCUAAGGACACCGAAGCCUAUGUGAAGGGGCUUCCACUGGCCAAACUCGGGACAAUCUGAGCAUCCUAACAAACAGUUACUAUUAAUGGAAUACAGUAUAGCCCUUUAAAUAGGGAACUACACACACACACACACACACACACACACACACACACACACACACACACACACCCCAAUACAUAUGAAUUGAUCUGAAAGUUUGCUGAGGAAGGGGUAUUUACAGAUUUUGAGAGUCUGCCACAAAACACUGUUCAGUUAGAAAGGGAAAGUCACACUGGAGAUGCCCAGCAGACACCGUCUUCACCAAGUGGUCAAAUGCACAUCAUCAGUAAUGGGCACUUUGAAAGUACGUGCCACCCAAGAGUGUCAGUGCUGUCACACUCCUGCCAAAGAUGCUUAGCCUGAAUCCAGUGCUGAGGAAACACCAGGCAAACACAAACUGAGGAACAUUCUACAAAUUCAGAACACUUCAAAAGUAUCCACGUCUUGGAAGUCAAAAAGCUUCCAAUCAGAAGGAGACCAAAGAGAUGACAACCAAGUGCAGCUCCUGCUCCUGAACUGGAUCCUUUUCCUAGAGGACAUGACUGGGCCUGAGGACCUGCUAGGAGUACUGCGUCCAUGCUGACUUCCUGUUCAGUGUCUGUAUCGUGGGCGGGUAGCAGACUCUCAGCAACUGACUCACACGGUUCAGGAAACAAAAUUCUUUGUAACGCACUUGCAUCUUUUCCUAAGUUUGAGAUUAAAAAAAACAAAAAACCCCA